GUGCUGGACCCGGACCUGUGUCCCCCAGCAGUGAAGGUUAUGUACUGGGAGGAAAAGAGGAAAGGCAUACUUGAGUGAGGCUGCGUGCAGGCUCUGGGGCGACUGGUUUGGUCGGCGAUGGGGGAGUGCCACUGUUGACAAACACUGGGUACGUUGCCGGGCGGCCCUAGCUCCCGUAGGCCCGGUCUGUUGCUAACAUCAAGGAGCUGUUUAUGGAGCCGCCUCCCCGUGGACUGGCCUUAAGUGUCCCUAUCUAUUCUCCCUACGACCAAAGCUCCUGCGGCCUUCCCUCUAGGGUUGUCACCCUAGCUGGACCUGGUUUCCGCAUGGGCCGGACCGUGGUCGUGCUGGGCGGAGGCAUCAGCGGCUUGGCCGCCAGUUACCACCUGAGCCGGGCCCCCUGCCCCCCUAAGGUGGUCCUAGUGGAGAGCAGUGAGCGUCUGGGAGGCUGGAUUCGCUCCGUUCGAGGCCCUAAUGGUGCUAUCUUUGAGCUUGGACCUCGGGGAAUUAGGCCAGCGGGAGCCCUAGGGGCCCGGACCUUGCUCCUGGCAUGUGGAGAGCAGGUUUCUGAGCUUGGCUUGGAUUCAGAAGUGCUGCCUGUCCGGGGAGACCACCCAGCUGCCCAGAACAGGUUCCUCUACGUGGGCGGUGCCCUGCAUGCCCUACCCACUGGCCUCAGGGGGCUACUCCGCCCUUCACCCCCCUUCUCCAAACCUCUGUUUUGGGCUGGGCUGAGGGAGCUGACCAAGCCCCGGGGCAAAGAGCCUGAUGAGACUGUGCACAGUUUUGCCCAGCGCCGCCUUGGACCUGAGGUGGCGUCUCUAGCCAUGGACAGUCUCUGCCGUGGAGUGUUUGCAGGCAACAGCCGUGAGCUCAGCAUCAGGUCCUGCUUUCCCAGUCUCUUCCAAGCUGAGCAAACCCAUCGUUCCAUAUUACUGGGCCUGCUGCUGGGGGCAGGGCGGACCCCACAGCCAGACUCAGCACUCAUUCGCCAGGCCUUGGCUGAGCGCUGGAGCCAGUGGUCACUUCGUGGAGGUCUAGAGAUGUUGCCUCAGGCCCUUGAAACCCACCUGACUAGUAGGGGGGUCAGUGUUCUCAGAGGCCAGCCGGUCUGUGGGCUCAGCCUCCAGGCAGAAGGGCGCUGGAAGGUAUCUCUAAGGGACAGCAGUCUGGAGGCUGACCACGUUAUUAGUGCCAUUCCAGCUUCAGUGCUCAGUGAGCUGCUCCCUGCUGAGGCUGCCCCUCUGGCUCGUGCCCUGAGUGCCAUCACUGCAGUGUCUGUAGCUGUGGUGAAUCUGCAGUACCAAGGAGCCCAUCUGCCUGUCCAGGGAUUUGGACAUUUGGUGCCAUCUUCAGAAGAUCCAGGAGUCCUGGGAAUCGUGUAUGACUCAGUUGCUUUCCCUGAGCAGGACGGGAGCCCCCCUGGCCUCAGAGUGACUGUGAUGCUGGGAGGUUCCUGGUUACAGACACUGGAGGCUAGUGGCUGUGUCUUAUCUCAGGAGCUGUUUCAACAGCGGGCCCAGGAAGCAGCUGCUACACAAUUAGGACUGAAGGAGAUGCCGAGCCACUGCUUGGUCCAUCUACACAAGACCAAGAACCAGUUGAAGUGGCGACAGAGUCAUGACAGGACCGUGGAGUGGCCUAAGGAGUACCCAGGGCGAAGUAGGAAACAGGCUCCUUCUAUUCUUCAUGUGCCUGGGUGCCAACUCCUCAGGUGCAGGGACCGUGACCACCUGGGGGCUGUAAGCGAACAGCCCCGGAGCUCGGCGGAGAGUAGGGUGGGGGUGGCGUCCUCUACCUUUUCUACCUUUCCCCUCUUCUAGCGGGGGUGGGGAGGAGGGUUACUGCUGAAGAGAAAGGGAGAGGGAGAGCAGGGGCAGAGACAGUCAGGGGUGGCUGGAAGGGCUCACCUAGAGGGGCGUGGUCCGCGCUGUGGAGGGGGUUAAAACCCAGCUCUUUCGGAGCACGCCCAUCCUAUCCCAGUCUCUUGCUUUUGCCCUACCUACUAGCAACGUGAGCCCGCCCGGCCCCCGUCCAUACUUCCACCUAGGACCCCGUCCCUGCUCAGGCUCGUCUCCAGGCGUUACCCAAAACUUCUCACUCUCUCGAAUGCCCAAACCUUUAUCCCAGGCCUCCGUGUCGACGCAUUCCCAGCGCACAUACCUGGUCUUUUGCUGCCUGUCGUCACCGCCACCCCAACAGCCGGGCAGGCAUCGCUGCCGCCAUCUUGGAAGCGGGCGCUGCGGGGGCGGGGUCUCGCGUCAUGGGGCGGGGCCUCGGGGCGGAGCCACCCGGGCUGACUAGGCACCCGGUCCCAGACACCGCGUGGCCGGGGGCUUGUGAGGGAGCAGCGCCUGAGCCUGCCCACCUGGAACGCGUUGUAGGCGACCCCCUGGGGAGCGGGUGCUAGGGUUCAACUCCACUACGCAGACUGCUAGUGGGAUUUCAUUUCCUGCCCCUCAGAUUUGUAAAAGCAGAAGCUCAAGCCCUUCAUUUUCCUCUGGGCCGAGACUGAUCAGGAGGCUAGUGAGCCGGUUUCUGGUGCUCCGCUGACCUCGUUAUCACCUUGUGGUUGGCUGAGCCCUCUCCCAGUGUGUCAGUGGCACCCCCUGCAGCCUAGUGCCACUUAGUAUCAAUUGUUCCUUACGCAGGCUACAGCGUUGCGGACCGCUCUAGCGCAUUUUUGUAUUCCCGUUGUAUCCCGCAGGCCUGGAAAUAAAAAGCGAUUAGUUAAUAAAACAAUGAAACAUUGAA